AAAAAAAAAGAAGGAACUUCUGUCUGGGGUGUGCCUAGCAGUCAUUCACACCCUCACUGAAAUCUCAGCUCCCUGGGAAAGGAUGUCGUGUUAAAGGGAGAGGAAAGAACAGACAGCGUGGGAGUCUGGGGUCUGAGCUGGGCCAGCCAUGGAGGUGAUGGGGCCCCCGACAGCCAGAGGCCAGAUGCAGCUUGAGGCUUUGUCCCGUACCACGCCUGUUGUGCUGUGGGGUGUACUUUGCCAUGCAUACCUUGCUCGCGUGCUGCGGGCAUUGGCUGUCCCAGCUUGGCCCCACUCUUGCAAAGUCAGCUUGUGCCAGGUAAGCAGGAAAAAGCCGAUGGCUUAUCUGAUUCCCGGCAAGGCAGAAGCAGGCUGGGAGGUGCGUGUGUGUACAUUAGCAUGUGUUUCAGCGUAUCCAGACCAGCUUCCGCCAGGAGCUAGGACCACCUUGGGCAGGUACAUGGUGACCCAUUUGACCUGCAGAUUCUUAGGAAACUUUUUGGAAACCAUAUGCCCACUUGCAGUGAGACACAGUGGUUAGGAGCAUGGAGCCAGUUGGCCUGGGUUGAACAGUUUAUUAGCUGUGUGGCCUGGGGCAAAUUACGCCCUGGGACUCUCACCCGCAAACCAGAGAUAAUAAUAGUACCUACCUCAUGGGGCUGUUAGGCAAAUUAAAUGAGGUCAGAUAAAUGCAAAGUGCUUAGAAUGGCGCUUGAUGUGUAAGAAGGGCUCGACAAGGUUCUCUAUUACUAUCAUUAUCUCCAGCCCAGGCCCAGGAAUGAGCUUCCACUCUAGUCAGGAUGGGUGAAGCCCUUCCUGGCUUAGCACCACCCUUCCAUCACCAUGACAACGCACAUCUCCUUGUGGGAGUGGGGGCAGCAUCAGGAGAACUGGAAGCCAGGAGCUGGCUGUGCACCUUAUCUGACCUGCUUCUAGAGGCUCCUGGGCACCUCCAGGACUUAAGGGGGUAGACUAGGACUUAUGGCACCCCAAAUGUGCUGGAUAACCCUGACUGGAGCAUGGCACCGAAGCUUCUUGACUCCAAAGCCACAGACUGGGGAGAACCCCGGAAUUCCUGAAAAUGUGGAGGGCCUUAGCUUUACCCUCUGAUUCGACCCCAGUCCCAAAGGGAACCUACAGGAUGCUCCGAGGGGUUGGGAAUUGGUGGGUCACACUCCCCAAGGACUUUUUAUACUGCGUCUGAAUGGUGUUUGCAUUUUUUUGCAAAUUGGUUGCUACCUUUAAAACUCAGGAAAUGGCACAUAAAAAAUUCAGGUAUCUGGCUUUUCUUUAAAGUGCCAGAAGAUCAAGCCACGGUGGUUGGCAUUCCUGCUGGGGCAAAAAUGCAGCUGCCCUUGGGCCAGGCCAUCACUCUGCAGUUCUUACCUCCCCUUCCCCUUGCCCUACCACCCUGCACCAGGCCUGCAGGCUUACCAUGUGUAACCACCUCUCUGAACUACAAGGGAAUCCAGAAAUUGGGGUGGGCAUUAUCCUGGCCCUCGGUGCCCUUGACCUGAGAUCAGUGCAGCCCAUCCCAAAUUCCUUUUUCCAGGACUCCCACAUACACCCACUUAGAACACAUCUGUGAGCCAGAUUUACUUCUUAGCACACUAAUAAAACAAUGAGCAGUCACCUAGGUUCAGGUAAUGGGUUGUACGAGCUCCCAGACCUUUCUAGAACAACUUAAGCCUCAGUCAUUCCUAAAAGCUGGGGGUGGAGGAUGGGGUGGGGAAGAAACCAUGCCAAGCAGUGAAAGGACUGAUAAUAGAAUAUUGCAGACACGCAGCCUUUCCUUCCCAAUCAAAAUGGAAGCAUUUGAAGGAAGGCUCUGGCUCAAGCCAGGGGGGCCUUGCUCUAAUGAGUCACCUACUGCGUCGCCGCUGGUCAGCCUGAUGUUGUUAGGAUGGAAAUGAGCUGGGGUUGCCAGAUUUGGCAAAUACAAAAACAGGACACCCAGGAGCAUUGAUGUUUUGGAUGAACAAUGGAAAAGAUUUUGGCGUAAAUAUGUCCUGUGGAAUAUUUGGGACACACAUAUUAAAAACGUAUUUGAAAUUUGGCCAGGCGCUGUGGCUCACACCUGUAAUCUCAGCACUUUGGGAGACCAAGGCUGGUGGAUCACCUGAGGCCAGGAGUUCGAUAUCAGCCUGGCCAACAUGGUGAAACCGCAUCUCUACAAAAAAUACAAAAAUUAGCCGGGUGGGGUGGCACAUGCCUGUCAUCCCAGCUACUUGGGAGGCUGAGGCAGGAGAUCACUUGAACCCAGGGGCAGAGGCUGCAGUGAGCCGAGAUCGCGCCACUGCACUCUAGCCUGGGCAACAAAGAGAGACUCCAUCUGAAAAAACAAAACAAAACAAAACAAAAUCUGAAAUUCACAUGCCACUGGGCAUCCUGUGUUUUAUCUGGCAAUCCUGAGAAGAGUCUUAGAAUGCUUGAAAAGAGCUUUAAACAUCAUUUCUUAAAAUGCCAAGCCUCCCUUUGGUGGCACUCCCCUUAUAGCUGAGUGUAAGCUCUGGAUGACAGGCACGUGGGUGCCAGGAGGCCAGGACCUAGGAGCGGGACGCUGACUCUCUGCAGCCCUCUCCUCUCACUCUCUUUUCCCUUCCAGUCACAGUCACUGCAGCAGACAUCAUGGCUGUGGAUGUGGCAGAAUACCAUCUGAGCGAGAGUGCCUGCCUGGAAUGCCCAGCGGGCCAGCACGCGGGGACCACCCAGCCGCAAAGGCAGUCUCAGCAUUGAGGACACCUUUGAGAGCAUCAGUGAACUGGGGCCUCUGGAGCUGAUGGGCCGGGAGUUGGACCUGGCCCCCUAUGGGACCCUCCGGAAGUCCCAGUCGGCCGACUCCCUGAACUCCAUCUCCUCCGUGAGCAACACCUUUGGGCAGGACUUCACACUGGGCCAGGUGGAGGUGAGCAUGGAGUACGACACUGCCUCCCACACGCUGAACGUGGCGGUGAUGCAGGGCAAGGACCUCCUGGAGCGGGAGGAGGCCAGCUUCGAGUCCUGCUUCAUGCGCGUCAGCCUGCUGCCGGACGAGCAGAUCGUGGGCAUUUCUCGGAUCCAGAGAAAUGCCUACUCCAUCUUCUUUGAUGAGAAGUUCUCCAUCCCCCUGGAUCCCACAGCCCUGGAGGAGAAGAGCCUGCGGUUUUCUGUAUUUGGCAUCGAUGAGGAUGAGCGCAACGUCAGCACGGGGGUGGUGGAGCUGAAGCUUUCUGUGCUUGACCUCCCGCUGCAGCCCUUCAGUGGCUGGCUCUAUUUACAGGACCAGAACAAGGCCGCCGAUGCUGUGGGGGAGAUCCUGCUCUCCCUCAGCUACCUCCCCACAGCCGAGCGCCUCACCGUGGUCGUGGUUAAGGCCAAGAACCUCAUCUGGACCAACGACAAGACCACAGCGGACCCCUUCGUCAAGGUGUACCUGCUGCAGGAUGGGAGGAAGAUGAGCAAAAAGAAGACAGCCGUGAAGAGGGAUGACCCCAACCCGGUGUUCAACGAAGCCAUGAUCUUCUCGGUGCCAGCCAUUGUGCUCCAGGACCUGUCUCUCCGCGUGACGGUGGCUGAGAGCAGCAGCGACGGCCGUGGGGACAACGUGGGCCAUGUCAUCAUUGGGCCGUCAGCCAGUGGCAUGGGAACCACACAUUGGAACCAGAUGUUGGCCACGCUGCGCAGGCCCGUGUCCAUGUGGCACGCUGUCCGGCGAAACUAGCAACCAGGGCGGGCCAGUUGGGCAAUGGAGCUGCUGGAGCCCGGUACCCACUCAGCUCUGUCUGAUGCCCUCUCCAUAGCCCAGCUGGAGCCGUGAACACUGGGGUCCCCUGGCAGAGUCCUCAUGACCCAUCCUGGUCUCUCUGUCCAGAUUGCAGCAGAGGAGUGGGCGUGGCUCUGUGUCCAGGGCCCCAGGGUCUGCUCCUGCUGAGGACCAGCUGUGGCUGGGCCAGGACAGAGGACUCAACCCUGCUCCUCCCGGUAGGCCAGCUGCCGAGCUGGGCUAUGUUCUGGAACCCAGUGAAUCUUGGGGGCCAGGCACUGUGCUAGGCACCAGCAGGGGUAACACGAAGAAGACCCGGCCCUUAGGGCAUCAGGAAGACUAGCUCCCCUGCCCCGGAGGAUCUGCUCAGUGCUGAUGGCAGCCCAGCUGUGUGGACUCAGGGGGCUCUGAGGGCUAGGGAAACAGGAAGGGCCUCUUUGACAAGGUAGGAGCUGUGCUUGGAGGGGCAGGAAAAGAACUGAGCAUGUCGCAGGCAGCGGGCCCAGCCUGAGCAAUGGCAGGAUGUGAACUUCCCCAUCGCAAAUGCAGUUCUCAGCCCACUGCAGUGGAUACAAGGAAGGGCCUUUCUCGGGGCCGGAGAAGAGACCAAGAGACCAGGCCCGGGCAGCAGCCUACCGGCCACGUGGAACACUGGCUCCGGAGUUAUUCUCUGUCAAAUCUACUCCCCGGACCUCAACCAUGGCAAGAACCAGAGGUCCAAAGAGGCCCAGACCCAGGUCCUUGUGCUCAGUCCUGCGCAAACCAGGCCCAGACCCUGCAAGCAUUUGUUGAUGCCCUUGCAGGCCCACUGGGAGAAAGAUGCCUCAGGCAGGUCUCAGCCUGGGGGUGGCAGGGGUGGGGCAGAGAGAAUACUGACAGCAGAGGUCUUGGUGGGCUGCACGUGCCUGCGAAGAUGUGGUGGACAAGGAGGCUCUCGGGCUGGGCCUUGGAGGGGUGGCAGCGGAAGGACAGCCCAGGUGGCUGAGGCCUGAUGGGAAGCCGGGGAAGGCCAGGGUGGAAGGGCGGCUUGAGGGACGCCAGGAGAAGACUGAAUGCCAGGCUAGGAAGGAGGCGGCUCUCGAUCACGGGGUGGGUGCCCCCGACACCGGGUCUCCUAGCUUGAGUUCCCUAGAAGCGAAAUCUGAGAGGGGGAUUCUGGGGCAAGUAGUUUCUUGCGGGUGAGUGUUCUCAGAGAAACUUACCAGAUCAAGAAAGGGAGCUCAGGCUGGAUGGAGGAAGCCACGCAAGUGUGGCUUCAAGAUCCAUCGCCUUGGCCUGAUCGCUGUGGGGGCAGGGGCCUGGAGUACGAGGGGCACCCUGGGGGCUCCCACCCAGAAGCAGAGGGGCUGGGCUGUUGCACCUCUACUGGCAUCAGUCUUUGGUUACCCCCCAGCCCCAGUAGGAGGAGAGCAGGCAGAGCUUGUCAUCCCCAGCCUGGUGUCCCGCAGUCCCAGGAAGCCGCUUCUUGCCUUCAUGGCUGAGUGCUGGGAAGGGCUGAGCUCACCCAGGCCAGCAGGUGGGGUAUCAUCUGCUCGGUGGGGCCACCCACAGGUGACAGCAUGGACCCUCAGGCUGGCUGCCCCUGUUCCUUGGUCCAUAACUGGUGAGCUAUGGAGACCCAGGCCAACAAAUUAUCCCCAGUGAUAUGGGGGGAGGAGGGGCUAGAACAAGGGCCCAGGGGACUGGAGGCAGGAUGGUGGCUUUCCCUACCUGACACAGCCAUGGCCCAGCCCCAAGGCCAGGCUGUCUACCCUAUGGCCACAGCAGGAGGUCAGCCCAGGGCCAGGAGACACAUGGCUGGACAAGGCUUUGCAGCCUGGGAGACCCCGACUUUCUCUAACCCAGUGGCUGUGCGGUGCAGGCCACUGACUCCCCCCCUGCCCUCUCCCCUCUCUCCCUCCCCCUAACUGCAUGACAUGUUAACUGUGUGCCCAGGACAGCCGUGGUGGGGACCGGGUAUGCCAACUGGAAUGAUUCUAGAACCAAAAUAAAGUUGGGGCAGGAAGAGGGGGCUUCCAGGGAGCCCUGCUCGGCCCUGAAUCACCUUCGUCUCUUCUCUAGGAA